GCAGGCUCCGAGCUGCUGCCCGCAGGAGGCAGGACGCGCAGGGGUGGGACCGGCGCCCCAGCCCGUCUCCCGGCCCCGGGCGCGCGGGAACCCCGGGUCCUGCAGCCUCCCGAGUGCGGAGAGGCGGGGCCGCCCGCUGCCGCCCGGCUGCCUGCGCCCCCUCCCGCGGCCCCGGCUCUGGGAGCGGGGCGCCCCGCGCGCGGGCACACGGCGGCCAGAGCGCCGAGGCGGUACCUUCAGCCUGCAAUGAGAGGAACCCGGGAGAGCCCCCGGGAGCCAGCGAAGAGCUUGGCUGCUGCGUCCAGGGCUGCUGCUGCCGCCGCGGCUGCUUGAAACUCCUCAAAGUUGAGAGCCGGCUAGAGGGUGCCGCCCGCCGGGAGCCGGAGGGAAAGGAAGUCGGAAGGUGCAAGAGUGACAGACACGGACAGACGGACGCGCAGACCUUCGGAAGGCACUGCGUAGGCAGCCUCCCCGGAGCCCACGAGGCUCCCCAGCACCGUGAGUUUUUUCCUGGAUGGGUGGUUGCUAAGUAUUUCCGUUUAAUUGUUUGUAGCGUACGUUUGCGUAUAGUUGUGUCUGUUGGAGGGAGUUUAAAACAACAACAACAACAACAACAACGCAGGAUGCACCUUAGGAAAAAAUUGAGUUUCUGAUGGUGGGUGAGACGGUGGGUUGUAUGGAGAGAAUGUGACUGUACAUUUUUAUAAGCAGGACUAACCCAGGAAAGAGGAAAAAAUACAUUUAACAGUGAAGAGGCAACACAGAGCUCCCUAUUGUGAAAUAAAACCCAUUUCAAAAGUUAUUGGAAAGAAAGUUCACUGGUGGGAGGCUGAGCCGGUGGAAAAGACACCGGGAAGAGACUCAGAGGCGACCAUAAUGUCGUUACGUGUACACACUCUGCCCACCCUGCUUGGAGCCGUCGUCAGACCGGGCUGCAGGGAGCUGCUGUGUUUGCUGAUGAUCACAGUGACUGUGGGCCCUGGUGCCUCUGGGGUGUGCCCCACCGCUUGCAUCUGUGCCACUGACAUCGUCAGCUGCACCAACAAAAACCUGUCCAAGGUGCCUGGGAACCUUUUCAGACUGAUUAAGAGACUGGACCUGAGUUAUAACAGAAUUGGGCUUCUGGAUUCUGAGUGGAUUCCAGUAUCGUUUGCAAAGCUGAACACCCUAAUUCUUCGUCAUAACAACAUCACCAGCAUUUCCACGGGCAGUUUUUCCACAACUCCAAAUUUGAAGUGUCUUGACUUAUCGUCCAAUAAGCUGAAGACGGUGAAAAAUGCUGUAUUCCAAGAGUUGAAGGUUCUGGAAGUGCUUCUGCUUUACAACAAUCACAUAUCCUAUCUCGAUCCUUCAGCGUUUGGAGGGCUCUCCCAGUUGCAGAAACUCUACUUAAGUGGAAAUUUUCUCACACAGUUUCCGAUGGAUUUGUAUGUUGGAAGGUUCAAGCUGGCAGAACUGAUGUUUUUAGAUGUUUCUUAUAACCGAAUUCCUUCCAUGCCAAUGCACCACAUAAAUUUAGUGCCAGGAAAACAGCUGAGAGGCAUCUACCUUCAUGGAAACCCAUUUGUCUGUGACUGUUCCCUGUACUCCUUGCUGGUCUUUUGGUAUCGUAGGCACUUUAGCUCAGUGAUGGAUUUUAAGAACGAUUACACCUGUCGCCUGUGGUCUGACUCCAGGCACUCGCGUCAGGUACUUCUGCUCCAGGAUAGCUUUAUGAAUUGCUCUGACAGCAUCAUCAAUGGUUCCUUUCGUGCGCUUGGCUUUAUUCAUGAGGCUCAGGUCGGGGAAAGACUGAUGGUCCACUGUGACAGCAAGACAGGUAAUGCAAAUACGGAUUUCAUCUGGGUGGGUCCAGAUAACAGACUGCUAGAGCCGGAUAAAGAGAUGGAAAACUUUUACGUGUUUCACAAUGGAAGUCUGGUUAUAGAAAGCCCUCGUUUUGAGGAUGCUGGAGUGUAUUCUUGUAUCGCAAUGAAUAAGCAACGCCUGUUAAAUGAAACUGUGGACGUCACAAUAAAUGUGAGCAAUUUCACUGUAAGCAGAUCCCAUGCUCAUGAGGCAUUUAACACAGCUUUUACCACUCUUGCUGCUUGCGUGGCCAGUAUCGUUUUGGUACUUUUGUACCUCUAUCUGACUCCAUGCCCCUGCAAGUGUAAAACCAAGAGACAGAAAAAUAUGCUACACCAAAGCAAUGCCCAUUCAUCGAUUCUCAGUCCUGGCCCCGCUAGUGAUGCCUCCGCUGAUGAACGGAAGGCAGGUGCAGGUAAAAGAGUGGUGUUUUUGGAACCCCUGAAGGAUACUGCAGCAGGGCAGAACGGGAAAGUCAGGCUCUUUCCCAGCGAGGCAGUGAUAGCUGAGGGCAUCCUAAAGUCCACGAGGGGGAAAUCUGACUCAGAUUCAGUCAAUUCAGUGUUUUCUGACACACCUUUUGUGGCGUCCACUUAAUUUGUGCCUAUAUUUGUAUGAUGUCAUAAUUUAAUCUGUUCAUAUUUAACUUUGUGUGUGGUCUGCAAAAUAAACAGCAGGACAGAAAUUGUGUUGUUUUGUUCUUUGAAAUACAACCAAAUUCUCUUAAAAUGAUUGGUAGGAAAUGAGGUAAAGUACUUCAGUUCCUCAAUGUGCCAUAGAAAGAUGGGGUUGUUUUCCAAAGUUUAAGUUCUAGAUCACAAUAUCUUAGCUUUUAGCACUAUUGGUAAUUUCAGAGUAGGCCCAAAGGUGAUAUGACUCCCAUUGUCCCUUUAUUUAGGAUAUUGAAAGAAAAAAUAAACUUUAUGUAUUAGUGUCCUUUAAAAAUAGACUUUGCUAACUUACUAGUACCAGAGUUAUUUUAAAGAAAAACACUAGUGUCCAAUUUCAUUUUUAAAAGAUGUAGAAAGAAGAAUCAAGCAUCAAUUAAUUAUAAAGCCUAAAGCAAAGUUAGAUUUGGGGGUUAUUCAGCCAAAAUUACCGUUUUAGACCAGAAUGAAUAGACUACACUGAUAAAAUGUACUGGAUAAUGCCACAUCCUAUAUGGUGUUAUAGAAAUAGUGCAAGGAAAGUACAUUUGUUUGCCUGUCUUUUCAUUUUGUACAUUCUUCCCAUUCUGUAUUCUUGUACAAAAGAUCUCAUUGAAAAUUUAAAGUCAUCAUAAUUUGUUGCCAUAAAUAUGUAAGUGUCAAUACCAAAAUGUCUGAGUAACUUCUUAAAUCCCUGUUCUAGCAAACUAAUAUUGGUUCAUGUGCUUGUGUAUAUGUAAAUCUUAAAUUAUGUGAACUAUUAAAUAGACCCUACUGUACUGUGCUUUGGACAUUUGAAUUAAUGUAAAUAUAUGUAAUCUGUGACUUGAUAUUUUGUUUUAUUUGGCUAUUUAAAAACAUAAAUCUAAAAUGUCUUAUGUUAUCAGAUUAUGCUAUUUUGUAUAAAGCACCACUGAUAGCAAAUCUCUCUCCAAAAUUCUUAAAGUUGAUUUUUUUAAAGGGGGAGGGGAAGGCUUUAAUGUGUUCUAGAUCAAUUUAUACCUUCCGUAUGACGUUUUACUCUGAUAUCAUUGUGCACUUUAGCCAGAUCCAGAAAACACUCAAAUUUAUUUUGCAACAAGUGAGAGCCCAGGAGACCUCCUUAUUAUCCUGUCUCUGCUUUGAGGCAAUCAAGUACCCUCUCUGAACCUAGGUUCCCUCAUCUGUAAAACAAAGGUUUCAGACCAGAUGGUGUUUAAGGUUUCUCCCCAUACUGGAAUGAAUGAUUUCUUGGUGGUAUUAGCAUCAUCACAGACCUAUACUUGCUUUCUGAAACUCUACCACAUACUGAAGGAAUACAGGAAUGGGAUUAAGAUGACUAGCAUAGCAGUGUACAGCUUGAAGAGAUGUUCCACAUCAUCACUCCAGCUCCUUCUCUUUUCUCAGGGACAAAUGAGGCCCAGAGAGAAUACGACCUGUGUAAGGUCAAACAGUGGCAGGGAAAGAAGGAGAGCUGGGGUUUAGCAUUCUCCCUGGUGAAGAUUGGAGGUCCAAAGAAAUGACUCCUUUUUAAGGGAUGGGCAUAAAAAAGUGAUCAAAACAUUGCAAAGGAGAAUCAAAGAUUGAUUGUCCUGGGGCUAAGAAAGAAGAUAAUUUUUAAAGAAUGGGAGUGGGCAACAGUGAAAAAUAUUGCAGAUAAGUAGAUAAGGAUAGAAGAUCAACCACUGACUGGUAGUA